AGUGAGGACGGGACUCUACUGCCGAGACCAGGCUCACGCUGAGAGGUGGGCCAUGACCUCCGAGACCUCUUCCGGAAGCCACUGUGCCAGGAGCAGGAUGCUGCGGCGACGGGCCCAGGAAGAGGACAGCACCGUCCUGAUCGAUGUGAGCCCCCCUGAGGCAGAGAAGAGGGGCUCUUACGGGAGCACAGCCCACGCCUCGGAGCCAGGUGGACAGCAAGCGGCCGCCUGCAGAGCUGGGAGUCCUGCCAAGCCCCGGAUCGCAGACUUCGUCCUCGUUUGGGAGGAGGACCUGAAGCUAGACAGGCAGCAGGACAGUGCCGCCCGGGACAGAACAGACAUGCACAGGACCUGGCGGGAGACUUUUCUGGAUAAUCUUCGUGCGGCUGGGCUGUGUGUAGACCAGGCUCUCACGGAGCCCUGGGUGCCUACAGCAGGACGUCCAGGACGGGAACACCACAGUGCACUACGCCCUCCUCAGCGCCUCCUGGGCUGUGCUCUGCUACUACGCCGAAGACCUGCGCCUGAAGCUGCCCUUGCAGGAGUUACCCAACCAGGCCUCCAACUGGUCGGCCGGCCUGCUGGCAUGGCUGGGCAUCCCCAACGUCCUGCUGGAGGUUGUGCCAGACGUACCCCCCGAGUACUACUCCUGCCGGUUCAGAGUGAACAAGCUGCCACGCUUCCUCCAAACCUUCUGCACUGUUCACAUGCCCACAGCUUCCUCGGGAGUGACAACCAGGACACCUUCUUCACAAGCACCAAGAGGCACCAAAUUCUGUUUGAGAUCCUGGCCAAGACCCCGUAUGGCCACGAGAAGAAAAACCUGCUUGGGAUCCACCAGCUGCUGGCAGAGGGUGUCCUCAGUGCCGCCUUCCCCCUGCAUGACGGCCCCUUCAAGACGCCCCCAGAGGGCCCGCAGGCUCCACGCCUCAACCAGCGCCAAGUCCUUUUCCAGCACUGGGCGCGCUGGGGCAAGUGGAACAAGUACCAGCCCCUGGACCACGUGCGCAGGUACUUCGGGGAGAAGGUGGCCCUCUACUUCGCCUGGCUCGGGUUUUACACAGGCUGGCUCCUGCCAGCGGCAGUGGUGGGCACACUGGUGUUCCUGGUGGGCUGCUUCCUGGUGUUCUCAGACAUACCCACGCAGGAACUGUGUGGCAGCAAGGACAGCUUCGAGAUGUGCCCACUUUGCCUCGACUGCCCUUUCUGGCUGCUCUCCAGCGCCUGUGCCCUGGCCCAGGUACGAGAAGAGGCCGGCCGGCUGUUCGACCACGGCGGCACCGUGUUCUUCAGCUUGUUCAUGGCACUGUGGGCCGUGCUGCUGCUGGAGUACUGGAAGCGGAAGAGCGCCACGCUGGCCUACCGCUGGGACUGCUCUGACUACGAGGACACUGAGGAGAGGCCUCGGCCCCAGUUUGCCGCCUCAGCCCCCAUGACAGCCCCGAACCCCAUCACGGGUGAGGACGAGCCCUACUUCCCUGAGAGGAGCCGCGCGCGCCGCAUGCUGGCCGGCUCUGUGGUGAUCGUGGUGAUGGUGGCCGUGGUGGUCAUGUGCCUCGUGUCUAUCAUCCUGUACCGUGCCAUCAUGGCCAUCGUGGUGUCCAGGUCGGGCAACACCCUUCUCGCAGCCUGGGCCUCUCGCAUCGCCAGCCUCACGGGGUCUGUAGUGAACCUCGUCUUCAUCCUCAUCCUCUCCAAGAUCUAUGUAUCCCUGGCCCACGUCCUGACACGAUGGGAAAUGCACCGCACCCAGACCAAGUUCGAGGACGCCUUCACCCUCAAGGUGUUCAUCUUCCAGUUCGUCAACUUCUACUCCUCACCCGUCUACAUUGCCUUCUUCAAGGGCAGGUUUGUGGGAUACCCAGGCAACUACCACACCUUGUUUGGAGUCCGCAAUGAGGAGUGCGCGGCUGGAGGCUGCCUGAUCGAGCUGGCACAGGAGCUCCUGGUCAUCAUGGUGGGCAAGCAGGUCAUCAACAACAUGCAGGAGGUCCUCAUCCCGAAGCUAAAGGGCUGGUGGCAGAAGUUCCGGCUUCGCUCCAAGAAGAGGAAGGCGGGAGCUUCUGCAGGGGCUAGCCAGGGGCCCUGGGAGGACGACUAUGAGCUUGUGCCCUGUGAGGGUCUGUUUGACGAGUACCUGGAAAUGGUGCUGCAGUUCGGCUUCGUCACCAUCUUCGUGGCCGCCUGUCCGCUCGCGCCGCUCUUCGCCCUGCUCAACAACUGGGUGGAGAUCCGCUUGGACGCGCGCAAGUUCGUCUGCGAGUACCGGCGCCCGGUGGCCGAGCGCGCCCAGGACAUCGGCAUCUGGUUCCACAUCCUGGCGGGCCUCACGCACCUGGCGGUCAUCAGCAACGCCUUCCUCCUGGCCUUCUCGUCCGACUUCCUGCCGCGCGCCUACUACCGGUGGACCCGCGCCCACGACCUGCGCGGCUUCCUCAACUUCACGCUGGCGCGAGCCCCGUCCUCCUUCGCCGCCGCGCACAACCGCACGUGCAGGUAUCGGGCUUUCCGGGAUGACGAUGGACAUUAUUCCCAGACCUACUGGAAUCUUCUUGCCAUCCGCCUGGCCUUCGUCAUUGUGUUUGAGCAUGUGGUUUUCUCCGUUGGCCGCCUCCUGGACCUCCUGGUGCCUGACAUCCCAGAGUCUGUGGAGAUCAAAGUGAAGCGGGAGUACUACCUGGCUAAGCAGGCACUGGCUGAGAAUGAGGUUCUUUUUGGAACGAACGGAACAAAGGAUGAGCAGCCCGAGGGCUCAGAGCUCAGCUCCCACUGGACACCCUUCACGGUUCCCAAGGCCAGCCAGCUGCAGCAGUGACGCCUGGAAGGACAUCUGGUGGUCCUUAGGGGAGUGGCCCCUCCUGAGCCCUGCGAGCAGCGUCCUUUUCCUCUUCCCUCAGGCAGCGGCUGUGUGAACCGCUGGCUGCUGUUGUGCCUCAUCUCUGGGCACAUUGCCUGCUUCCCCCCAGCGCCGGCUUCUCUCCUCAGAGCGCCUGUCACUCCAUCCCCGGCAGGGAGGGACCGUCAGCUCACAAGGCCCUCUUUGUUUCCUGCUCCCAGACAUAAGCCCAAGGGGCCCCUGCACCCAAGGGACCCUGUCCCUCGGUGGCCUCCCCAGGCCCCUGGACACGACAGUUCUCCUCAGGCAGGUGGGCUUUGUGGUCCUCGCCGCCCCUGGCCACAUCGCCCUCUCCUCUUACACCUGGUGACCUUCGAAUGUUUCAGAGCGCAGGGCCGUUCUCCCUCGUGUCCUCUGGACCCACCCGCCCCUUCCUGCCCUGUUUGCGCAGGGACAUCACCCACAUGCCCCAGCUCUCGGACCCUGCAGCUCUGUGUCCCAGGCCACAGCAAAGGUCUGUUGAACCCCUCCCUCCAUUCCCAGUUAUCUGGGUCCUCUGGAUUCUUCUGUUUCUUGAAUCAGGCUCUGCUUUCCCCCUAGCCACUACAGGCAGCCUCUGACAGUGCCGCUUUACUUGCAUUCUGCAGCAAUUACAUGUGUCCUUUUGAUCCUUGCCCAACUUCCCUCCCUCUCCCAGCUCCUGGCCCCUGGCCCAGGGCCCCUCUUGCUGUUUUUACCUCUGUUCCUUGGGGCCUAGUACCCAGCAAGCACCCAAAUGGGGGAGGUUUUGGGAUGAGAGGAGGAAACGUGUAUACCUGUAACAUCUGGUGGCUCUUCCCCCAGAAGUUUGUGUUCAUACAUAAUUGUUUUCCACGCUGGAUCAUAAUGUGACGUGCAGUUCUGCCCUGUGCUGGGGAGCCACAUGAAGCUUCCCCUGGCUAACUUGCUACCCCGCAGCAAUCCCAGUGUGGCCGUCUGCUUGCUAAAAAAUGGAUCUGUGCUCAUCUGUAUUGAUGUCCUUGGAGUUCUACAAGUGGAACUUAAGUGUCAAAAAGAAUAUGUGGUUUUUAGCUGAGCGUGGUGGCUCACACCUGUAAUCCCAGGACUUUGGGAGGCUGAGGCAGGAGGAUUACAAGGUCAGGAGUUCGGGACUAGCCUGUCCAACAUGGUGAAACCCUGUCUUUACUAAAAAUGCAAAAAUUAUUCUGGGUGUGGUGGCGGGCAUCUGUAAUCCCAGCUAUUUGGGAGGCUGAGGCAGGAGAAUCGUUUGAACCCGGGAGGCGGAGGUUGUAGUGAGCUGAGAUCUCAACACUGCACUACAGCCUGGGCGACAGAGCAAGACUCCGUCUCGGGAACACACACACACAAAAAGAAUAUGUGGUUUUAAUGUGCUUUGAUGAGUACUGCCAAACUUACUCCACAGAAAAGGCCUCUUUCUGAACAUCCUCGCCUGCGUUCUAUUUCACCCACCGUGAUGCCUGGCCUGAGGGCGGCGUGCUUGCUUGUAGCAUUUCUUGAGGAUUUGCUACUUGUUCACCUGCCUCUUAGGAGCACUGUGCCCUGCCUCCAUGGAAGGGCUCUUCCGGCAGGGAUGCAGGCUCACAGCGCCCUGGGGCUGGACACCACCGGCCGGAGCAUGGCGGACAGCACACACGGCCCGGGGCGGGAACCUUGGAAACUUUACACAGAUGGGGAGCUCAGCCAUUCCACGUGUGCUUUCGCUCAGCACAAUGCUUACUACAAACCCACGUGUACUUCCUUCCAGCUGGUUGCUUUUUAUUGUUGCUGUCUUAAACUCCAAA